GCGCAUGCGCGUCACUAGACGACACGGCUGUCUUCUUUCCUGGAGAAUUUCUCAAGGACUGCUGGCUGGAAACUUAACGGCUAAUGUGGAUCUGACCGUAGUUUGCCAAAUUAAGAAAACGUUUUUACCCUGUUGAAGAUUUGCUUUAACUUCAAAAGUGAUGACAAGAAAGUAUGGACACCCCUUCAGGACCAACCUGAUAAGUCACUGGGACCAUUAAAAAUCUUUAAUUGUGCCAGAUGUUUCUGACUACCGAGUCAACAUUCACUGAUUGAGCCAUGAAGAUUGAGCUAUGAUGAUACUGCCAUCUUUCUAUCCAUUACAAAUGUAAAGUUUUUUUCUAGCUUUCUAUCUCUAUGGGCAAGUGUGGUCUCAAUGGAAGGUGAGCAAUGAGUGUAGGUGUGGGAUAUGACAUCAUUUUAAUUUUUUAAGUGUUUAUGUUCUCUUACAAAUUUAUACUGCAGAGAUGGUCUUUUACCACUAUGAGCCAUAUAACGUGAUGUACAUAGCAGUUGCUUGAAAAACAUUUGCACUUCUUGAUGAUAGAUGAGGACUUUGUAGUUGCUUAUUUUUUGUCAUCUUUAUGGAACUAACAUGGUAACAGUUAUAUCCUAAUAGAAAAAAGUUAAAGUCCUAAAAUCAUCCAGGUCAUUCUUAAGCAGGGCUGGAAUGUCUCAGAAUUUAGUAGCUAUUCUUCACCAAGCAGAACUUAGUCAUACCACUGUGGACUUCCCUUAUUUUCUCCUAUUUGCCACAAAAAAAGCAAGUGAAAUAAUGUAAGAGAGGGAUAAGGAGAUGUGGCUACUGUUUAACAACCCAUCCAGUUGUUGGCUCGUGGCUUUCAUCCAGAUGAGAAUGAUUAGGAAUGACUCCAAAGGCCAAAAAAUGUUUAUAUUCCAUAAUGUGACAUUAAACAUUUCUGAAUCCAAAGUCUGAAUUUUAUUUUUCUCAAAAGCCAUUUGCACUAAUGUUUGUAUUAUAAACAUGUCCCUCAAAGAGGUUGAGCUAGAAAUGGUAUUAUCUGAUGGAGGGGCUAGACAUAUAGAUAUGUAACCAGUUAUCUUUUCUAUCCUAUGUUCUUAUAACAGAAGCUACCUUCUUUGAAGCUGUGUUGAGGUGUUGAUAGAAAGUGCAUUUCUUUUGUACUGCUUGUGAUAAAGGAACUCAUGGCCAGGUUAAUAUUACAUAUAAACAUGUUUAAGUACAGACUGUAAUAGAGGCUCCACGAGGUCAGGGAUUUUUGUGUUUUUUUGUUCUCUUAUGUAUCCCAAGACCUAAAACAGUACCUAACACAUAGUAAUUACUAAGGAAAUAGUUACUGAAUGAAAGACUAGAAUAUGGUCACAUUAUUCUUGCAUUUUGUUUUCUUUGGCUAUGCAAGUUGUAUCAUAUUUUCCUGUUUUCAUAAUCAUCUUCUGAAUAUUGAUUAAUACUUAGUCAUAUGAAGAAAUAUUAAUAUAAGAUAUAGAAUAGUCUUAACAAUCAAGAUAGAAAAAACAUUUAUACCCCAAGUGUUUUCUUUCUUUUCCUUUUUUCUAUUUAUCUUAAAUAGGUUGAUUAUGUUUUGAUUUCAUUGUAUAAUACACUGUUGAGGUCAAACAAACGAAGCUUUAGUGAAGAUUAUUUUGAAAGAAACAAUAGAGCAUUUAAUAAUUUUAUUUGCAAAAUAUAUUUCAGAAACAUUUUAUUUCUAGCCUUAAACAGAAAUCUUAAUAAUAUCUUCUACAUUAUGCAGGCAGCAAACUGUGAGAUAGGCAUGCCCAAGCAUUUCUAGGGAAGGACUUAUACAUUCUUAAUAGCAAUUUUAAUUGUUCCCAGAAUUGAGAAUUUUUAUUCUAAUAAUGACAUGGGUAAUAUGCCAAUAAGAUACAUAUUAAAGGUGAGACCUAAAAUUCAUCUUGCAAAAUAAAAUUAUUCACAAAUGACUUUCUGAAAUACCUCUUUAGGAUUCUUCUUUGCUUUCCAGGCUGUUCCACGAAAUUUUUGCUGCUAUUACUUUAGUAUGCUACUACACCCCUUCCCACUGCUUACUUUAAGAAAAUCCCCUCACACUGAAUACGCACAUAUACAUUUUGUAAUGUUAAUUCUAGUCUGUCUUUUCAGUUAUCUUCUUGGCACAAAUAUCACCUCUAAUAAACACCAUUAAUCAUAAUGAUGGUAUUAAUAUCAAUAACAAUGAUUACCCAUUCUAGAUUAGUUUAUUCAUUUUCAUUGACUUAAAAUGAUUACUUCUUGACUUGAGAGGUAAGUAGUUCCUUAGAGACCUCUGAGACUAGUGAGAAUAGAGCAAAGAGGCCAACUGUUAGGCUUGUCAGACUUCCUUUUUUAUGCUGGGCUAUGCCCCUUUUCGCAGUUUCACUUGGAUGAAGAACUGGAGAUUUAGUAGUUAGUGUCUUUGCAGUGUGGGAGUGUCUAACUUGGGAAGUCAUAGAAGAAUGAGGGAAAGUCUUAUCUAUUUAUUUCUCUGGUAUUUUUCUGGUAGCUGAAUUGAUUUAAUUUUACCCGUGAGAGAUUACACAUCAUUAAGGAUUGUGAGUGAGGCAAAUGGCUAUUUAAAGGUUGACAGUGUGAAAAAACUAAUUAAAACAUGCACAGUCUAAUCAGAAAGAAAAUAUAUGAGAAAAGGGGAGAAUGUAAAAAUGGUUAAGUUAUUAAGCAUGCACAAGAUCUCAGGAUAGUAUCUCCAUCUUAUUGCUACAUAUUUCACCAAAUAAGGAUUAUUUUUUUCUUAUCUCAUGGUAACAUCAAAUGAAUAAGUUCAAAUUUACAUCUACAAACCAGAGAUUAAAUAUGUCAAUAAAAAAGUGAAAUAUCUGUUGGAAAUGAUAAUCAUAAAUUAAGUAAGCCAUAAAUAGAAUUUCAAUGAGGUGUUUUGAUUUGUGUGAAUGAAUUCAUUAAAUAAAUAUUAUAGCAGCAAGUUAGAGGCCUGUAAUAUACUGACUAACUACCUAGUGGGAUUCUUUUCCACUGCAUUCCAAAUUUAUAAGAAAUACGCAAAAAUUAAGUAAAGAAAUAGGUCUCAGAGAUUAUUAACUUUUAUGUCAUGUAGACUUAAAUACAGUUUUAAUGAACAGAACUGAAGAAAAAUUGAAUUAUAUUUACCAUUUUUUAUGCUUAGAAAAGUGGCUUCAAUUUAUUAAGAAAGAAUCUUGAAAUGGAAGAUUGAAACUAAGUAUGAAUUGUCUGUUUAAUUUACUGUUAUCUCAAAAUAUUAAAUUUAUUAAAUACUGUAUUCACAAAGUGUUACUGAGAUAGGACGUGGGAUGCAACUGUGGAGGGGCUCAGACACUGGGACACAAUGGGGACUAGGUAAAACAGGGAUGGGGCAGAAACAUCUCUCCAUAAGACAAGCCCACCAAUGUGCCAUGUCAGUUUACCAUUGCCAUGGCAACAUCUGUAAGUUACUGCCCCUUUCCAUGUCAAUAACCUAACAGCAUGAAAGUUACCACUCUUUUUCUAGAAAUUUCUGCAUAAUCUGUCCCUUAAUUUGCAUAUAAUUAAAAGUGGGUAUACAUAUGACUGCAGGACUGCCUCUGAGCUGCUAUUCUGGGCACACUGCAUAUAGGAUAGCCGUACUCUCCAAGAAACAGCACCUCCGCUGCUGCUGUAUGCUGUCACUUCAAUAAAAGUUGAUGUCUAACACCACCAGCUCACCCUUGAAUGUUUUCCUUAGCAAAGCCAAGAACCCUCCUGGGCUAAGCCCCAAUUUUAAGACUUGUCUGCCCUGCACCUUUAUGAUCAAUGCAAGAGUCUCCUGUACAAUAAGGUAUACAAAUAGCAGCAGAUGGUCUACUGAAUAAUUGAACAUCUUUCAACUUCACUUGGCCUGUUAGGACUACCCUUCACCUGGUACUUUUCUAACAGUUGACUUAGUUGUUGGGCUAAAGCUAAAAGGGGCCAGAGAUAAUUUUAAUUUCUUUUCUCUCUCACUGGAAUAGAGGUCUCACAAGGUCAAGGCUCCACAAGGCUCAGUGCUAAAGGAGAGGAAUCUUAAAAAUGGUUUUUCUUUCGUUUAAAGAUGACACACUCUGAAAUUAAUUUGAUUUUGAGAUUUGAGAACUUGGACAUACAUACUUCCUAUGGAAGGAGUCAUGCUAUACUGAAAAGACACUUCAUCAAGAUAACUCUGGGAGAAGCAGAAAACCCUGUGCCAGGGACAGGAAAGAUAGGAGAAAGAAAGUUUAUCAGAAUUUUUUAAACCUGUCUCAGAAAUAACAACAUAUUUUAAUCAGAGAUUUGCUGAAGCUUCAGAGAUCACCUGCCAAACACAGGCUGAACCUGACAGCAUGUCACACCAGGAUGUUGCUAUGAGGACAGAUUCAUCAAAAAUGACUGACGUGGAGUCUGGGGUCGCCAAUUUUGCAUCUUCAGCAAGGGCAGGCCGCCGGAAUGCCUUACCAGACAUCCAGAGUUCAGCUGCCACAGACGGAACCUCAGAUUUGCCCCUCAAACUGGAGGCUCUCUCCGUGAAGGAAGAUGCAAAAGAGAAAGAUGAAAAAACAACACAAGACCAAUUGGAAAAGCCUCAAAAUGAAGAAAAAUGAAGGCUCAUAAUCUAUCAAGAGUGCUGAAUUUCUGCAUGUUGAAAGACUUAGUGGUUCUGUUUUCUUGAGACAUUUAAUCUGGUGGUAACUGUGGUAACAUUGCAGCCCUAAGCAGCAUGUGUAUAUUAGAUAAUUGUGUUGUGAUGCUACUCACUUUGAUUGCAAUGAUGAUGUCCAAGGUAAGCUAUUAAAAGGCAGGUUACUUCCAAAUCGCACUGAAGGAAAAGGUUAAGAAUAAUACAUGAUCACAGAAAUGCAUACCACUGUCUGUAAACCCAACAAAAUUCACUGUUCUCUUUUGGAUUUAUUUAGCCUGAUGUAUUUUUAAUUCAAUUUUUAUGGUGAUGGGCAAAUCAUUCUUGGUAAAUGUAAAUCAAACAUGAUUGAUUUAAAACUUCAUGGAAUUUGUAGAAAAUUAUGGACAUUUUUGGUGAGAAAGAACAAUAGUCAAAACUCACAUGGAUAGAGUGUGUUUGUUUUUUGCCAAAAAUGCCCCAGACUUUUUCCCAAACCUCAAAAACGUCUUGGAAAAAUUGUAAAAGUUUGAUAACAGAAACAUCUUUAGGAUAUUUUUGUCUGACAUAUUUUGCUUCUAGUAUGUGCCUACUGUGAUUUUUUUCAUGUGGAAAAUGCAAAAUUUGUAACAAAAUGGUUAUAUGGAACAUGCCUAUUAAAUGAAUUUUACUAUCUUCCCUAACUUUGGUCUGUGUAUGUGUGUGUGUUUUACUUUAAUAUGAAUUAUACAAAAUACUAGUUGUUUUACACUCUCUUUUCUUAUUCUUAGGGCUUUUGUGUAUGUCUGACUUGUUUUUAAAUAACUUCCUCAGCAAUGCAGACCUUAAUUUUUAUAUUUUUUUAAAGUAGCUAACAUAGCAGUAGGCACUUAAGCAUUUAGUCAAUGAUAUUGGUAGAAAUAGUAAAAUACAUCCUUUAAAUAUAUAUCUAAGCAUAUAUUUUAAAAGGAGCAAAAAUAAAACCAAAGUGUUAGUAAAUUUUGAUUUAUUAGAUAUUUUAGAAAAAUAAUAGAAUUCUGAAGUUUUAAAAAUGUCAGUAAUUAAUUUAUUUUCAUUUUCAGAAAUAUAUGCAUGCAGUUAUGUUUUAUUUGAUUGUUGACUUAGGCUAUGUCUGUAUACAGUAACCAAAUAAACUCUUUCACUAUUAAAGAGAUUUCUUACUGA